GGCCGGCGCGCUCGGGCGGGGACGGCGGCGCCGCGGGGGCCGCAUCCUCGGUGCCGACCCGGGAAAGUUUGGGAAGUCGCCGCAGCGGCUUCGCAGCGGCGGGGGACGCGCGGCCCGGGUCGCCCUCCGCGCCGCGCUCGCCCUCUCCGCGCCGCUGCUGAAUAAUUCAUGGCGCGGCCGCCGGCCAUUAGCAUGCACCGGGCGCGCGGCGCGUCUGUGCCAAGCCGCCGCCGCAUUCGGCGCCCGGGCAGCGCCAGACGAGCGGCCGCGCGGCGGCCGGGCCCACGCUGUCCCCGCGCCCGCCCGUCCGGCGGCGCCCAUUGUGCCCCGGCCCGCCCCGCCGGGCUGUCCCCAAGCCCGCCUGCAACCCACCGCCCGCCCGACGGCCCGGCCCUGCAAGUCCUGGCUCGCGACGCCCGCCCCGGAAUGCACGUGAACUUGGAGAAAGUCGCGGGGCGCGCCGGCCGGGCUCUCCGCGGCAGGGCGUGGGCGUCCCGGGGCCGGCGCGCUUUCGUUUUCGUCUGGGACAAAGGUCCCUUGCGGCGCGCGGACGCCGUGACCGGGUCCUGCGGGCCACUCUGUGGCGCAGUCGGGUCGCUAAGCGCAGGGAAGCCGGAGCCCGAAGGCAAGGAGAGACGCGGCGCGGGGCCGGGGAAGUGGGGCCUGGGCCGUGCGCUUCGCCCGCGGCAGUCCAGAGCCGUCCCACCCUGCGAAGAGUUGCGGGAACUGGCACCGCUCUGCCGUCCGCCGCUUCGACGCGGGAAGAGGGUGAGCGUUUGGAACCCAGGACUCAGACCGCUAGCUGAGGGCCUGUGCAGCUCUGGGCACGCGAGCGCGGCGCCGGCGGCGGCCAGGCACGGUCCUCCCGCAAGGGCAGGGCUGUCGACCUGUGCGCCCCAGGUCACGAUCGGGUUCACGGCGACUCCUGAGGACGAAUGUGGCCCCGUCCCAGAGCACCACCCGAGACAUCAGGAGCCCAUCGUGGGCUAGGGAAGAUCCUCCGGGACCUAACGGCCCAGGUAGCUGCGUCUUUACUCCCCGCCUGGGCAGGGAAGGACUCACUCCAGUCACAAGCAGCCUGGAGAUGGAUGGUUUGGCAGAGAAGGGGAAACCCCAGCACCAACCCAGCCCCAGGCCCCACCUUGCAGCCAGGUCUGCCCUGCCCAGAGUCCUCGAGGGGCUCAGCCUGACCCUGACAGGUAGAAGAGACCCCACUCCAGGCCCAGAAGUGAGGGAGUAGAGCAAAGGGUCCCUGGCCUACUGUGUGACCACUACCUGCCGCCCUGCCCAGUGGGACAGGGAUGCCCCGCACCCAGCCUCCUCACCAUCCAGGUGGCCUGGGGGCACCCAAGGCUUCGGGCAGCCCCUGAGCUGGGCCCAGGUCUCAUGGCGGUCUCAGGGCAGGCAGGGUGAGAGCUGACAGGGAACAGAUGAGGGAAGAGCACCCCACACACCCGGGGGUUCCACCAUAAGACUUCCUCAGCGUUUCUCUUUCCUUCCAGGUCUUCCACCCUUGGCCACCUCCCCAGGUGAUGCCUGAAGCUCAAGGGACUGUGUCCACCCUCAGGUCAGUACAGUUUGUGAAUGUUGAUGAAAAUUGGGGCUCCCCACAUCCCUCCCUUCUGGCUCCACCCUCUGCCGGGCGUGCCUGAAACUGGACACACACACACACACAGCACACACGUGUAUAUGCACCAGCCCCAGAGCUCUGGGGGCCAAGGAGCCAGGCAGGUGCUUGCUGCCCAUUGGCACGGGCUCAGCUGGAUCUAGCCCGGCCUCCUGCUCCUUGCCCCUACCAGCCUCUUUCUGCGGCCACCAGCCUCUUUCUUUCUGCAACUGAGGGACCAGGGCUCCAAGCAGCUGGGUUUGGUCCAGGUCUGGCCCUGUUUUUUGGGCUCCCUUCUGCCUGAGUUGGGUGACACUCCUGUUUGCAAGGAUCCAGCUGUCUCAAGGGCCCUGGGAGGGGAGGCCAGGGGCAGCCUAGGGGACCAGUGACUACAGGGCAAUUUGCAGUACCUGCUGGGGGCUCAGCAGGUAAGAUGUCCCCUGCCUGCUGCUGUCUGUCAUGGCUGUCUGGUGGCCAUGGCCGGGGGCGGGCUUGUCAUGCUGGGAACUGCUCAGAGGCUGCGGCCAGCCUGAGGCCCCUCGCCCUGGCGAGCCAGCCCCCGAGUGCAGACUGUCGCCGAUGAUUCUUGCCUCCUGGGGCAUCCGUGCGGCCAUGUGGGUUGGGCAGGACUGGCAUUCUCCCCUCCCCACCGUUGCCAUGGCCAGGGGCGGGCCCACCUCCCGAGGCUGUGCGGAGAGGACCCCAGGCUGCUGCAUGUGAGCAGAGCAGCCGGUGUCUGGCCCGGACCCCUCUGCCAUCUGGGGCCCGGCGUGUUUACAGGUCGGCCUUGCCCGCCAGACUCUGCAGACGCUGCCCCGGGGCCUUUGUGUCUGCACGCAGGGCUGAGCCACCAGCCGAGCGGAGAGUGGGGAGGGACACAGGUGGGGAGUAGGGGGAGGCCCCUGGGGGAAUCAGGGAGGAGGGGCAGGACAGAAGAGAAAGGGGAUGAAGGGUAACAGAGGAAGGAGAACAGCGUGGGGACAGGAGAGGGGCAGGGACUGGGGAAGAGGAGACACAAGGCAGGACAGGGCAGGGCAGCCCUUGGAACUGUGGGGCUGUCACAGGGAUACCAGCCUGGGGGAGCAGCUAACCCCAGGCAUCUGACAGGGACCUAGUGGGUCUUGGCCAAGGCGAUCUGGUCAACGGAACUGGGGUUUUCCUGGCACCCACCAUAAGCCCAGGCCUGCCCGUGGGACCUCAUCCCACCUGUACCCAGCCCUCCCUGUAUACACAGCUGGCCACCACCUAAUGUAAUCCCUCUGACAUCCCACAGGCAGCAGUGUUGGUCUCUAGGGUCCAAAUGAAACAGACCCCACAGGCGUGUCCCUCACACAGGACUGAGCAUGGAAUGUGCCCCUCCCUGAGUCUCUGACUCCCAAGCCUGGACUGACAUGUCCAGGGAGGCUGCAAGGGUGUGUCCCCUGGAUCAUGGGCAGGGGGCACCGUGUGCAGCUGCUGAGGCUCAGGAUGUGUGGGAAAGGGCCUGGAGUGGAGGAGAAGAGGCCUGCAGGGGAGUGGACAGUCCAGGGCUGGGACCAGCACCCCAAUAUGCAUGAUCCGUGGAAGAUGAGGCUGGUCGCACACAGAAGGUGCUUACUCAGUGCUCGUCAGAUGCCAGAUGCUGGCGUAAUCACCACAGGGGUCACACACCCUCCGUUAGGACCACCAGCAAGGCAGGGCCACCGUCCCACACUGUUCUUGCAGAGACGGAGACUGGGGAUCAGGAGCCUGGCCCUACUCUGGCCUGCAGCCUUGGGGGCUGCUGGGGCUGUGGAGGGCCUCUGGGGUGCUGGCUUGGACUGGGGGAGCCAUUGAAGGUCCAUGGGGACCGGGACUCCUUCAGCAGCGUUUGUUUUUUAGCUGACUCAAAACUGCUCCCCUUGGAGGCCUUGGCCCAGGAUGGGGAAGCCUCAGCCGGGCAGGUCCCUCGGCCUUGCCCACCUCUCAUGGGCCUCACGCUCAGGAGGUGGCAUCCUGCUGGCCACACCAUGGCAUUAGCCCCGUGCCUCACCCACACUUGGUGGCAAUAACAGGAGCCACAGCCCCAACCAGAGCCGGCGGCCGCGUGGCCCCCUUGAUACCCGGCACUGGCUGGUUUUCUGAAGGGACUCGUUCCUGUUCUGGGUACCCUGGGUUCUGGCUGAUGGAGAGGCCGCCCUGUCCUUCAGGAGUGGGUGCAGAUGUGGGUGCAUGGGAAACCCAGACGUGAGACGGGUGAUGGCUUGGCACCCCAUGGCAGAACCAUGCUGAGAAGCCACAUCGGCCAGCUCCAAGACUGCCUAAUGGACCUGGCAUCCACAGCCUGAGAAUGGGCCCCGGGGGACCACAGUGUGACCUCAGCAGCCUCUGCAGAUGGUGGAGUGGCACUUUUUCUUCUCCCGAGAGGUUGAAGGGCAUCAGCAGCGGCCCCAGGUGGCCUCCACAUGCAGGUCGAGGGGACAGAGGUUUGUUCUCAUGUCAAAUACCCAGACGCCUUUUUAAAUUUUUUUUAAUGUUUUUAUUUUCUAUUUUUUUGGAGACGGGAGUCUCACUCUGUCUCCCAGGCUGGAGUGCAGUGGUGCGAUCUCGGCUCACUGCAACCUCUGCCUCCCGGGUUCAAGUGAUUCUCCUGCCUCAGCCUCCAGAGUAGCUGAGAUUACAGGUGCCUGCCUCACACCAGGCUAAUUUUUGUAUUUCUAGUAGAGACGGAGUUUCACCAUGUUGGCCAGGCUGGUCUUGAGCUCCUGACCUCAGCUGGUCUGCCCGCCUUGGCCUAAAGUGCUGGGAUUACAGGUGUGAGCCACUGCGCCCAGCCUGAUGCCUUUUUAUACCCAGACAGAAGCAAGCAAGCCCUUACAAUGGCCCUGCAUUUGAUCUUUCAGUCCUGCUGAAAAUGCAGAUGCUUCCUGACUUGCAGUGGGGUUUGUCCUGAGAAACCCACUGUAAAUUGAAAAUAUUGUAAGUCAAAAAAGCAUUUAAUACACCUAACUACCAAACAUCAUAUCUCAGCUCAGCCUCCCUGAAACGUGCUCAGAACACUUAUGUUAGCCUCUAGUUGGGCAAAAUCAUCUAACACAAAGCCUAUUCAUGAUAAAGUGUUGAAGAUCUCCUGUUAUUUAUUCAACACUGUACUGAAGUGUGGUUGGUUUCUACUGAAUUCAUAUCCCUUUGGGUUGAGAAAUCUUAAGUUGGAUCCUGGUAAGUCGGGGCUGUCUUUAUGGACAAAAUGCAGAGUGAUGGCCCUCACGCGGCACCUCCCUGUUGGCUUUGAGCAGCACUCUCUGUCUGGGAGAAACUUUAGUGAGCAUGAAGUUGAGCCCUCACCGUGAUGAGGGAUGGGACAGGGUGCAAGGACAGCCACCUGCUGUUGCAGGUUUCACCUGGGUGAAACACCUUCUUGAUUCGGUUCAGAUUUGUUAGGAGUUCCUGUGGGCCAAGCCCUGAGCCAGUCACAUGGAGUCAUCCCUCUUCCUGAUGGCCCUGCUGAGUGCCCCUCCCCUGAGGCUCCCAGAGCCCACGGGGCUUGCCCUGGCCACCAGGCUGGCAUACAGCAGAGCAGGGCCCUGGCCCCAAGCUGCCCCGCAGUAGAAACACCUCUGGGUUCCAUGAACGUUGUCUCGCCAAGGUGUGGGGCCACCAGAUCCCUCAGGGGCGGGGAAGGUCUGGGGUCUGGGCCGAGCCUUCCGAAGUCUGGCUGUGCAGUGGGUUCAGGCCCUGCCACUCAGACCCUUGCCGGGAUGGUGCCGGGGUGGGCCAGGCCCCCAGCCCCAGUGCUCCUGGCAGUGGCCAAGGCUGCUGCCUCCUCAGCUCUGGCUUCCCUCCCUGGCCUGGUUGGUUGGGCACCUGGCCUCAGGCAUGGCCCAGGCUGGGGGCCUUGCUCCCCACACAGUAGUGAGCUGAAAGCACUGCCAUGUCCAGCUCUGGGAAGGAGCAGGCUCCCAGUUCAUCCCGCAGCCUCGUGUCGCUGCUCCAGCUGUCCCGGGUACGACGUGCCCUUCUCCAAAAACACCUCACCCACCCAGCUGGGCUGGCCUCGAGAACUGGGGAGUCAGAGGCCCUUGGCUGUCCCUGAAAAAGGAAAACGGGCCUCCUGAUGGGGGCUUCCUGGGCUCACCCAACACAGAAGGACCUCCUAGUGCCCGUGCGCCGGCAGGUAAACCUCUUUGGGUCCCCGUUCCCUCAUCCCUGAAACAUGGGGAGCACAGUUGCUCCUGCGCUGGCUGUGGCUGUGGGGGAAGGAAGAGCCGCUCCAUUCCUGCGUUUGAUCAGGUUGUCACGAGGACUGAGUGAGUCACCAGGUGUGAGGGGCUUUGGUGGGUGUGUCACAGUGGCAAAGCAUUCACACCGGCCAGGUCCCCAGCUGGGAGCAUGUGCCCAGGAGCCUGCGGUGUGCAGCUGGUCUAGCCCCACCGUGGAGCAGCCACGUGGGAGAGGCCCCGGGAACAGGCGAGGUGGCUGUGCCGUUCACACCCAGAGAGUCGUCAGGGCAACUGGUGACACGGUGAUGGGGACAGUGGCACCUGCCCUUGAUGCUGCCCUGUGUCACCCAGGCAGCCCCCACCCCAUGAACACUGUGCAGGCUUUUCCCUAAUUUCAUUCUUGUUUUUUGAUGAAGGCCCUGCCCGUGGCUCUGGAUCGGCGGUCCCCAUCAGAGGCCUGGGCUGAGUCCUCAGGUGUGUGAGUACCAUCUUCCCCUGACCCGGCGGCCCCACAAACACCCCUCUGCCAGCCACAGCUCGGCCGCCCUGGGCCUUGGCCUCCCAGUCUGUGCAGUGGGGUUGGUGACGAUCACAGGCUUCUGCUCUGUGCAGGUCGGGAGGGAGUGCCAUGUGGCUGCACCCCCAGCCCAAGAGCAGCCUCGCUGCUGGACCUUUGGGUUCCCAAUAAGAUCUGGUGAAGACACAUGGAGACCACUGCUGGGCGGGGGCAGGAAGGCGUCCCUGUGGCACCCUGGGGCCGCCCAUCUGUUGGAUCUGGAGGUGCUGCCUGCCAGGCUCUACUCUGCAUCCAGCGAGUGUUUGUUGGGGGCAAUGGGGCCCGUGCCUUUUGUCCAGAGGAGGCCGGAGAAGGGGACACAAGAGGGGAGUGGACAGACGGUCACCAGGCAGAUAAGCAGGACGGGGCUCGGGGCUUGUUUGGGAAGUGGCUGGUGCUGAGCUUGGCUGGGGCAGGGCUCCAGGAGGGGCCGAGUGGGCCCCACCCCCGACCCUUGUCGGCAGGGCCCCGAAAGUUCCACGCUGUUGGGGGGGUGCCGUGGAAGGUGGAGCGGGGAGCAGCCUCCGAUCCCUGGAGCAGGUUCCCCAGCGUUCCCGUGGCAGCCACUUCAUGGCACAGUGGUCCCCGGAGUUCAGGCCAGGCCCUCGAGCCGCCUGUCUGGGGACCACUCCAACCUCAGGCAAAUGAGGGGCGGCCCUCCCCGGGUCUGGGGGCAAAAGAAGGUUUUGAAUCCGGAAGCCCAGGCUCAGUAGGCCCUUGCCACCUCCCCCAGAGGUCAUGCCUCAGGCUAGGCCACCUGGGCUGCAACAUGGGAGGGCAUCAGUGCCCCAGGCAGCCCCCAGUCCCCCGGGGCCACUGCAAGACCCUUAGACGGGACGACAAGGCCUCUAGAAGCCCCGGCUGCUGGGAGCCUAGGCAGAAGAAGGGCCCACCUGCCUGUCUCUGGGGCCGUGCGCGGGGCGGGCACUGUGCUGCUUUUCCGGUGGCUCCUGCUCCUCCCGGCCCCAUCACCACUCCCACCCGCGGCGGCCUUUGUCUUCCAAGCGCUCUGCAAAAUGGCCGCCCGGCCUGCCGCCAUUUUGUGGCUGAGGUGGCCGUGGCCUUGGAGAGGCCUGGGAGGGAGGGCGGCCAUGGCCUGCCUGCCUGCCCUUGGCGGCCUGGACAGAGCCCAGCGCCGGCCCCCGCCCAGUCUGGCCUUGGCCGUGGCUGCCCCAGGCUUGGCACCAGCCAGCCUUUGGCAAGGCAGCCCGGGAGUCCUGGCCCCUCACCCAGCCCUGCCGGCCCCUCGCCACCCUGAGGCAGCCCUGCUGAGCAGACGGAGAAGCCUUGAGCCAGGGCCGGGCCAGUACAGCCUCGCUGGCGGGGGAGCCCUGGGCCGAGGGCAGCUCAGGCGGGUGUGGGGCCCACCUGGGCUCCCGGCACCUCUGCAGGGGUGACGCCUUCAGGCCUUGACGGCUGCACCUAUCGCGCUCCUGGCCUGGCCCGGCCGGGAGUGGGUCUCUCAGUGGCCGGCCCAACUUCUGGCUUAGAGAGGGGCACCGCCAUCCUCAGGAAGAGGGCAGGGCCGCACUCUGGCCAGGAUUUCCCUGUGUUGGGGCCAGCCAAAGUCUCUGACACACAGGAGUGGAGGACCUGUUCCCUCCUGGGCCCCUCCACAGCCCCCACUCUCCUGCAGGCCCCAUCCCCGCAACCUCAGCCAUUCCAGACAGCAUCUCCCUCCCCACCAGAGCCCCUCGGCCUCUCCUGAGCCUCUGAGCUUGCUUCCUGCCCCGUCACAGGCCCAUGCACCUGCCCUUCCAGUAGCCAGAGGAUCCCAAGUGGCACAUUUCCGAAGGGACGGUCUCCAGGAACCCCCAGGGGCCAGGGUGGCUGCAGAGCAGCAUCAGGGAGAUGCUGGGUGUUGGCCGUGGAGGACAAUUGUGCCCCUGGCCAGGCGGGGAGGGGGCAGGUGGACCCUGUGGGAGCCCUGUGGGAGCCCUGUGGGGUUGGCCACACAUCGGUUCCUGCUAUCCUUGCAACAAGAUCCCCUGGAGGGCAGUGUGCCUCCUAGAAGAAGGCAGGAGAAAUCACCACGUGAAGCAGAGAAUGGCGUUUGAUGAGUGUGUGCUUUUUCUAGGGGUCGACGCAGGUCCUCUGGGCAGCAUGGGGUGGUGCCGGGUGGACCCCACGGUGGCCUGUGUUCGCCACGUGGCCGUGGGUCAGUUCCUCGCUGGAGGAGACCCUUCCCCAGACACCUGCCGGGCACCCAGCCAAACCCUUGAGGCCUGGGAAGGUCUCUGGAUGCCACCCUACACCCCGCCCAGACUCCUCUCCCUGUGGUUCCUGGACAGAACAUUCCGUCACCACGAAACGAAGUUUGCCCAGGCCCUGCCUUCACCCUGGGAAAACCCAGCCGGGCAUGGGAAGGAGGAAUGCUGCCCGCCUGCCCGCCCAGACCAGAGUCGCCCCACAUGCCAGGCCAGGCCCGCAUCCUCCUGGGGCACACGGGAGCCCCAGGCUUCCCGGCAGGAAAAGCCCCCCACCGCAGAAGGGCUGGUCUCUGGUGGGGAGUUGCUGCUGGGUGGGGUGACCACAGGGCGGGGUUCAGGCUGGGGUAUUUUUAAUGAUGUAGUUGCAUCUGGUCACCGCCCCCUGCCACCCCCGAUUCUUUCCUGCCCUCCCCACCUUGUGACCCAGACUGUGGCUUGAAUUAAGAAUGUUUUCAGAUAAGUACACGCCUUUGAGGUUAAAAGUAUGCCUAAUGAUUAAACACCAGACAGAGAUCCCCACAGGAGAAGAGCGGGCUCCGCAUUCCUGCUUUUCCCCUUUGGACUCCAAGCAAGCCUGUUUGCGUAACCCGGGAGCAUUAAAGAGCAGCUUCCCCGGAUUCUCCCCACAGCCCUGGGGGCUGGCGUCCUGACCCAUCAUACGGAGGAGGCAGCUGAGGCCCAGAGGGGUUAACCUACCCCAUCCCAGGCCCAUCACUGAGGGAGACAGAGCAGGUCAGAACCAAGCCUGGCAGCCCCCAGGGCUGUGCCCCAUGGACGCAGGUGUGUCUGCAGAGCAGGGUCCUCCCCUGCCAGUGCCAGCCCUCAGGUGUCUCGGGUGCUGCGUUACUCUUGUGAGCUUCCACGCUGACACCUGUGGCCACAAUGUUGGUGUCUGCUGGACCUCUGGCCCUGUUCUAGGUGCAGGACAUGUGGCCACAGCAGGCCUGGCCCCUGCCCCAGGGAGUGGACAUUCCCUGAGCCUGCCCCCCACCCCCACUGAGAACUUAGUGGCUAUGAGAGAACAGGAAAGCAGGAAGCUAGACAGGGCACAGACCCCCGACGGUGGAGACCCUGACCCGGAGCACGUGGGUGUCAGUUUUGGGGAAGCCAGACAGGGAGGGUGCUAACAGGAGGGCCAGUGAGGGGACCUUGGGACCCCAGACAGCCCUGGAAGGAAGGCAGCCCUGGAAGGAAGGCAGCCCUGGGGUCCGGGCCACGCUCCAUCCUGGGGGCACCCCCUUCCCACCUGCGUGCAGUGUGCAGGGCCGGGGGAGGAGCCUGGAUCUGAGGAGUGCAGUUCCAGUUGUGGCUUUGCCGCGGCGUCCCCAUGGCAUGCUGUUGGGGACCGUGAGACUGUGGGCGGCCUAGCUGUAUUGCAGCCUGAGGCCAGAGGAGAGGUCAGUAACCCUUACCCGUCCCAUCUUGAUUUAAGUUUGAUAUUUUUAGAUCAUGGACGUUUCUGCAUUGAUUUUCUUUUUUAAUUUUGCAAUCAGAUAUUUCUGCUGAUGGCUGGGUUUUUGGUCCUUUUAACAUGCUUCCCACACCUCGCCCUGGUCCCUGCCCUGCUGCGGCCGAGCCAGAGCCGCAGGCUGCCCCGUGUGUGUCUCGUUAGCUUUCUGGGCCGUGUUUGCAGGAGGCCCGCCUCCCGUCCUAGCCCCCGGACGCCACCCCUCCCUGUCUUUUUCCCAGAUCCAUUGUUGGCACGGCUUGCUGAGCAGAGACACUGGCCGCUUUAUGGGGAGAAACCCAAUCAGGGUGGCGGGGGUGUGCUCCUUGGGGGGGUCCGGCUCCCAGUGGCCCUGAGCCAAGCCCGAGGUGACUUCGGGGUGACACCGUCUGUCUGCCUCACUUGCUCCAGACAUCCGCCCGGCCCUGAAAUGGCCACCUGCCCACCGAGGCCUCCGCACACCUGUCCUGGCUGGCCCGGCCCCUCCCCCGCCUGGGCCUGCCGGGCACCCUGCCCACGGGCAGACACCGUGGGGCCGGGGCAGCGCCCGGGAGGUGGCAGCUGGCAGAUGGCAGAGCGCCUGCCGACUGCUCACUCCCCGUCAGCUCUGCUCAAGGAGCACCGUUUACGCUGCAUGGCCCUCCCAGCCCUCAUCCAGGCUGGCUGCGAAGGGUUUCUCUGGUCUGUCUCAGGAAGCCUCCUGAGAAAGGGGAGAUUCCUGCUGUCUCCCCAGGCCUGAGCCCCAUGCUCACCCCCAGGGCUGCCAGGUAGGUGGGCCUGGAGAUCACCCCCGCACACACCCCACAACACGUGCAACUGGCCUUCUCCCCACCAGCUCAGAAAUGGCUCCAUGAGUGGGUCACGAAGCUGAAACAUCAGUCUUUCCCCACCCCACACCCCAGAAAGCCCUGGUUGUCGGCUGGAGUUCUCCUGAUUGCGUGCAGAUCCUCCUGCGGUGGGGGUGGAGCCCGCUGAGGUCACAGCAUCUGUGUCCUGGUCCUGUGGAGCACAGCAGGGUUGGGUGUGCAGGAAAUGUGUCCAUACACCCUCCUCAGAGUCCCCCGGAGCGGGCACUGCCACAUUCAGGCUCCCUGACCACUGCAGGCCUGGGUGGUCCAGAUGCGAGUCCUAGAGCCUUGCGGGCAGAGCUGGGACUCACCAGGGAACACAGGGCCCUCAGGGGAAAGGAGCAGGAAAAAGCAGGGUGGUUGUGCCUGGCAGAGGGACAGGCCAGGGCAAUGCUGGGAGCAGAGGCCUGCCCGGGACACUUGCUGCUCUGGGAGGCUGGAGGGGGAGCCCGGGCUGCGGGCAUGCUGGGGAGGGGCAGAGACAGUAGAGAGGGUGUCAACAGUGGUAGACGGCCUAGCUGGCUGGGAGCGUGGGCAGGGCUGGUGCUCAGGGAGGAGGAGGGAAGGGCACCCCCCACCCAGUGUCCCCACAGGCCCCUCAAUAGCCUGGUGGGUGACUCUCCCGGUCCCCAGCAGGGCUGCUCUUGCUCGAGGUCACACGGUACAGGGCUGCAGGGAACCACGGUAUGUCUGCUCCCAUCCAGCGUCUUGGGCUCAGCCCCGGGGACCCACAUCCCUUCCUGCCUGGAUGCACCUCCCUGGCCUUUGCACCCCGUGCGCACCCUGCAAGGGCACUCCUGCCAGAAUGGGCUGGCGUGAGGUGAAGUUUUCAUUCACUGGACAAGACCUUGCCGAAGCCCUGCAGCCCCAGACUGGAUGCUGUGGGCCCCUCCCGGGGGUUUCCGCUCGUGGGAGAACCCCAAGCCUUCCUCGUCCUGGGUCCCAGGGGAAGCCACAGCCCCCCUGGACCCUCAGCAUCCUCCUCGGUGCAAUGGGGGCUUAACCCCUCCCUCCAUAGUCCAGCCACCUGCUGACAGGCCAGGCACCCGGGAAAGCAGCACCAGGCUGUCCCCCCUGUGCAUCCUGCUGCCCUCCUCUGGGCCCUAGAGCAUCCAGGCACCAGCCUGGCAGGGCACAGGCUUCCCAGCAGGGGGACAUGACCACUGACCACUCAAGGACAGGCUUGGGUCUUGGUCCCCUCUGACCUGGCAUUGUCCAACACAGGGCUGGCCACGGAGGCCAUUCCACAUUCCAUCCAGGCCCUUACAGGGGUGGGUGAGCCACUAGGCGAGAGACGGGCCAGGCUGGAGUGUCGGUUCUGGUGCGGGACGGCUGGGCAAGGCCCAAGGUCACAAAGGGGUUCAGAGCUGGGUAAGGCCACGUCUCUUCCAGAGCUGACACUUGUCACUUUUGUUUUUAAAACCCAACAGGUCAAGAAGUGGCGCUGACCUGGAGCCCCUGCCUGGGGCUGGCCUUCCUCACAGUGAGCUGGGCCUCCUGCCAUCCUGGCUCUGGAGGUAGGAGGAGCCGUGGGAGGUCUGAUAGGGAGGGAGGGCUAUCUCAGAGCCAGGCCACUCCCGGUCCUCUCCAGGCCCCACCCUCAGGCACAGAGGUCCUUAGGUGGGGACUUGAUGGUCUCACAGCCAAACCUUCGCCCAGGCUGUGGCCUCCCCUGAAGCCAUGUCUCUUCUUGUCUUCCCGCCACUCUUCCAGCAAGCUCCCCCCGUUGGCCCACCUCAUCUGCCCACUGUGCACUUGGGGCAUGGUGAUCUUUGACCCUGGUGGUGCACCCCUCAGGCUGGACAGGGCCUGAAGGAGCCGUGGUUCAUUGCAGGGCGUCUGAGUGGAAGAGGCUCAGCCUCACCUCCACACCCUGAAGACUCACUCUCUGGCCCUGGGCUCUGUUGUGUGCACCGCCUGUCUGCAGGGCCCAGCCUGCCUCGAGCACUCCCUGGGGACAGAAGCUCCUGCGCUGGCCUCUCCUGUCACCUAGCCACCGGGCAUCCUGGAGUGCAGCCCUCAUGCCCCGAGGCCACCUGCCAUCGCCCAGGAUGACUCAAGAUGCCACCUGGGUAAGUCUAGCCCAGAACGAGAAAGGCCGAAUGAGGGAAACUGAGUCACAUCUGCUUCUCCCAGGUGGGGCUGGGGGCCCAGGGGGAGGGCACUUGUGGUGACGACCAGGGUGGACUAGGGGCCUGUCUCCCAUUCUGUCUCUGCCACACGUUAUAGAGCCCGACCUGUGGGCUGGGUCCCCCCAUGGUGAGCACUGUAGGCUCUAGGAGGCUGAAGUCCUGGCCUGGGGGACCUGUGGGGGCCAGGCUGGGGCCAUUGGAAUCAGUAUGGUGGUCCCCACCUGCACUCCAGCUCCGAUGGCUGAUGACGGGGGCCCUGGCAGCUGACCCCUUGCCUCAGUGGGGAGACCACGGCUCACGAGGGCAUGAGACCUGCCCAGAGCAUAGCCCAGAGGCCGGCCUGGAUUCUCACAGCUCCGCCCACUGGGCUGUCCUGCCCCACCCCCUUUUUAGCCUGCUGGGACCAUGAGUCAGAACCCAGUAGGUGUGAGGGGACCCAGCCAGCCCAGGUGGCCAGUCCAGCCUGAGGGGGUGGGGGUCUCAGAGAUUAAGUCAGGAGCCCAGAGUGCGUGCUUAGGGUGCAACCCACCCCACAGCCUCCCCCAAGGCACCUCCCGGGGGUGCAGAUGGGGGCAGACGCAGGGACACUCAGGGUGGACCACCUGACUGGGAGCUGAUCAUGAGGUGUGCGACAGCCUGAGUCAGCCUCAGCUCAGAGGAGCUGGGAUGGCCUUGAUCUUCCCCCUCCGGCCACUCACCACAGCUGGGAGGGUCCAAGGAGACCCUCAGCCACUGUCCCUUCAGCCCUCACCCCACCCUGGCUGGCUCUGCCCGGACAGUCCUUAGGGACAUCUUGGUCCUGCCCACCAGCCAGGGGACCCAGAAUUGGAGCAGGGGAGCAGGACCCCCAGACCCUCUCAUACCGCUUUUGUUCUGAGGCCUUGAGGGAACACGGGGUCUUCGCGACCCCAGGCGAGAUGAUGCUGGGACAGAGGAGGGUCGGGCUGCAUCGGGGCCCUCCUGGUCCCCACUCCUGGGUGAGUCAGCAUCUCAGUCUCCAGUUCUGGGUGGGCGGCACCAGGUGUGAGCCUCAGCGGUCUCCUUGCUGGCUAAGGACCUGGGAUUUGCUCCAGUGCCCCUCGGGAGGGAGUAGGACACGUGCCCAGAGAGCAAGCAGACCCCCUCCCCGACCAACUUCUGAGAGCAAAGACACCUAGAGCUAGAGAUUCAGCACCCCCUGAGCCUCAGUUUCUCCACUAUGAAGUGGGAUCCGUGAUCUCAGCCUUACCAGGGCUGUGAGGAUUAAAUGGUCCAGCCCAGCCUGGGGCCUGCCUGGAGUAGGCAGCCUGCUCAGGAUGGGCUGUGGAAGGAGGGCUGGGGUAGACCUUUCAAGUCCACUUGGGCAUGGGGAGCUGAGAGCUAGCAUGCCGUUUAACUUGGCAGGAAGCAGGCCGGGCGCAGUGGCUCAUGCCUGUAAUCCCAGCACUUUGGGAGGCUGAGGCGGGCGGAUCACGAGGUCAGGAGAUCAACACCAUCCUGGCUAACACGGUGAAACCCCCUGUCUACUAAAAAUACAAAAAAUCAGCCGGGCGUAGUGGCGGGCGCCUGUAGUCCCAGCUACUCGGGAGGCUGAGGCAGGAGAAUGGCGUGAACCCAGGAGGCGGAGCUUGCAGUGAGCCGAGAUCGCGCCACUGCACUCCAGCCUGGGGGACAGAGUGAGACUCCAUCUCAAAAAAAAAAAAAAAAAAAAAAAAAAAAGCUUGGCAGGGAGCAGGACAUUUGGACCUCACUCUGCUGCCCCCUUGGCUGUGUGACAUCCAGGUCACGUUGCCUCUCUGGGCCUCGGUCUCCUCACCUGUUUAAGAGGGGUUGACAGUCGUAUCUGCCCCCUCAGCUUUUCCCCAGGAAGGUGGUAGCCACAAUUAGCAUUUGUUGAGGCUGACCCUGCACCAGGCCCAGGAUAGGCGGGGCUUAGGGAGGCCCGUCUCUCGCCACGUUCCCCUGCUAGGGGAGCCCCGAGGCCCUCUCAGUGUCAUCCUCAUGCUACACUCUGUCCCAGCCCUGUGCGUCCCAAGCUAGGGCACUGAGUGUGCCAGCACCCGCAGGGACAGGCACUGGACCCUGGGUGGACCUGAGGGUCUGUGACUACCCCCCCAGCUGCUCUCCCCUAGAGGCCACUUCCCUCAAGGAAGGAAAGAACCUUCCCGCCACCUCCUGCAGUGCGGUCAGCUCAGGCCAGCCUGCACAGCAGGGCCAGAACCAGGGCCCCUGGGGAGGGAUGCCUGCCUGCCCAGUGGGAGGAGACGGCACGCCCGUGAAGCCGCUACUCAGCCAGCCUGGGGGCCACGAGUGCUGCUUCUGGUGGCGCUGUGCGGGGAGGGAGGGGGCCGAGCAGGGUGGGCACUCGCAUGCCUGUGUCUUGCUGGCCUUCGACAGAUGACAGCCCUCCUCCUAGGGUCUCCAGUGCAGAGUUCCUUGGGGACAUUAUGGCCACUCCUGUCCAGAUGAGAGGGAGCCGGCUGCCUGUGACAGCGUCGCAAAAUGCCGCCAGGGCUUUCCCUCCCUCCUCCUUUCUCUCUUCCUCGUCCCUCUCUGGUUGGUGGUUUCCUGCAGGCUCCCGUCCCUGCUGGUGCUGGCCACAAUGUCCCCACUCCCAGGGUUUCGGCGUCCCAGCCCCCUGCGCCCACCGCGCCUGCCCGCCAGAAUCCCUGUGCCCUUGGUGCGUGUGGCCUGCCGAGCCUCGAGCCCCUGUUCUCCUCAGCCCUCUUUCCUCCCGCGUCCCCAGGAGGUGCCUCUGGAAGCCACGGAGUCCCAUCGGCACCAAGACCGACUGCCCUUUGGGGUGAGGUAGUAGGUUGUAUAGUUUGGGGCUCUGCCCUGCUAUGGGAUAACUAUACAAUCUACUGUCUUUCCUGAAGUGGCUGUAAUAUCUGCGGUGGACAGAGCGUCUGGAACCCUGGCUGGGAGCGGGCAGGGCCAGGUUUGGGGGCAGCCUUGGCAGCAGUCGGGGGCAGGGGCCGCCUACACUGAGAAGUCUGACAGGCCUAGGUGCCACUUGCUGUGUGACCUUGGACAGGCCCCUGAUCUCUCUGGGUCUCAGUUUCCUCCUCUGUAAAAUGGAGGCAAAUGAGGAUGGAAGGAGAUGCAGUGUGGAGCAUCGAGGGCAGAGGAGAGCUGAGCCGACCCCACCCUCUGCCCCAGCCGCACUGAGAGAGGCGAUCCACGCAGCUGUUUGUCUGACCUCUGUCUCCCAACACUCCCCAACACUCCCCCCGCCAUCAGGCCCAGGCUCAUGGGUGGCCCUGAGCCGUACCCUCCACUGAGCACCAGGAGAAGGCACCGUGGGGCCAGGGGUGGCCGAGACGUUUGGAGGUCACAGGGCUGCGAGUAUUGGCGUUGCCCAUCACCCCAGGUUCCCAGCACGUGCCCCAGCCUGGCCAGCUCAGUGGCAGGGCCUCUGCCUGUGGAGGAAGGGAGGCCAAGGCACCUUUCCUGAGCAGGAAGUGAGAGGAACAGCUCUGCAUACACUGGGUCCCACAUGGCACAAUCUGAAGGCAGACAGUGGCUCCUCUGUACCUGGGGAAACUGAGGCCCAGAGAGCCAGGGACUUCCCAAGACCAGCCAGCAGCAGCUGCCCCUUCCUGGGGUGCCAUCUCCCCUGUCCCUCCUGCCCUGCGCCUGCCCAGCCCUCCUGCUCUGGUGACUGAGGACCGCCAGGCAGGGGCUGGUGCUGGGCGGGGGGCGGCGGGCCCUCCCGCAGUGCAAGGCCGGGCCUGGCGGGGUGAGGUAGUAGGUUGUGUGGUUUCAGGGCAGUGAUGUUGCCCCUCGGAAGAUAACUAUACAACCUACUGCCUUCCCUGAGGAGCCCAGUGACACGACCCCAUGGGAGGGCCGCCCCCUACCUCAGUGACACGACCCCACGGGAGGGCUGCCCCCCACCUCAGUGACCUGCAGGGGGCCUGAGCCGAAGCUGGGUGGGCAUCUGGGAGCUAGAUUCAAUAAAGCUGUUCUGACCAUGAA